AGAGACUCUGCUGCUUUUCCUGGGCAGGGCCUGCUUGCUCCAGCUCUCAAGUCUGACUUGCAUCUACACUGCGGGCAAGAUGUGGCUGCAAGACCGCAUCGCCACGUUCUUCUUCCCAAAAGGCAUGAUGCUCACCACGGCUGCGCUGAUGCUCUUCUUCUUACACCUGGGCAUCUUCAUCAGAGACGUGCACAACUUCUGCAUCACCUACCACUAUGACCACAUGAGCUUUCACUACACGGUCGUCCUGAUGUUCUCCCAGGUGAUCAGCAUCUGCUGGGCUGCCAUGGGGUCACUCUAUGCUGAGAUGACAGAAAACAAGUACGUCUGCUUCUCCGCCCUGACCAUCCUGAUGCUCAACGGAGCCAUGUUCUUCAACCGCCUGUCCUUGGAGUUUCUGGCCAUCGAGUACCGGGAGGAGCACCACUGAGGCCUGGGGAGUCGGAACAGGGCUAAGGAGGGGGAAGCAAAAGGCUGCCUCGGGUGUUUUAAUAAAGUUGUUGUUUAUU